AUUCUCCUGCCUCAGCCUCCCGAGUAGCUGGAACUCCUGACCUCAUGAUCCGCCCACCUCGGCCUCCCAAAGUGCUGGGAUUACAGGCAUGAUCCACCGCGCCCGGCCUGACCUGUGGAUUUUUAAGGACUGAGCUUCAGUCAUUGUCUAUUCCUGGAACUUACCAAGAGAAGAUCACCCACCUGGGACAUUCUCUGAUGAGUUUAACAGGUCUGAAAUCUUUGGAUCUCUCGCGCAACUCCUUGGUUAGUCUGGAGGGCAUUCAGUACCUGACUGCAUUGGAGAGUCUCAAUCUCUACUACAACUGCAUCUCCUCGUUGGCAGAAGUGUUUCGGCUCCACGCCUUAACCGAGCUCGUGGAUGUGGACUUCCGGCUGAACCCCGUGGUGAAGGUUGAGCCUGACUACCGCCUUUUUGUUGUGCACCUGCUCCCCAAGCUCCAGCAGCUGGACGAUCGCCCCGUGAGAGCAAGCGAGCGGAAGGCUUCCCGACUGCAUUUUGCAUCAGAGGACUCACUCGACUCCAAAGAGAGCGUCCCAGCUUCUUUGAAAGAGGGCAGACCACACCACCCCAGAGCCAAGUGCACCGAGGCCUUGGCCAAGCAGAGCCUGGUCAUGGAUGCGGAUGACGAGGCAGUCCUGAACCUCAUUGCAGAGUGCGAGUGGGACCUCGGCAGGCCUCCCGGGAGCACGAGCUUCAGCCAGAAGGGGCGUGAGGCCGACUCUCGUGGUUCCCAAGAAUCCAGACAUCUGUUGAGCCCGCAGUUGGUACAGUACCAGUGUGGGGACUCUGGGAAGCAGGGCCGUGAGACGAGGAGGAGCAGCUGCAGAGGGUGCUGUCUGGAGAAGAUGCCUUGGAGCCAGCUCUGUGGAGAGCUUCCGCCACUGUACGGAGCGGAGCCAGAGGCCUCCCGUGCCCCCAGGCCACACACGUACUUCACCCCACACCCAGACUCCAUGGAUACCGAGGACUCGGCCUCUUCUCAGAAGUUGGAUUUGUCAGGAGAAAUGGUGCCUGGUCCCCUGCCAGCCCCCGGAAAGUGCAGGAAGCGAAGAAUGCCUGUUGGAAGAUUCCAGACGUUUUCGGACCAGGAGGGUUUGGGCUGCCCGGAGAGAACUCAUGGGUCCUCCGUGCCCAAGGAGAGCCUGAGCAGACAGGACAGCUCAGAAAGCAGGAACGGGAGGACCUUGUCUCAGCCUGAGGCCUCGGAGACUGAGGAGCAGAGGUCUCGGGGUGUGACCGACACCAGAGAGCCGUCUCCCGGGUCACACUCGGCUCUACCCGGGAAGAAGACGGCCCUGCAGGCGGCGCUCCUGGAGACGCUCUUGGACCUGGUGGACAGGAGCUGGGGCGGCUGCAGGUCCCUGCACAGCAACGAGGCAUUCCUUGCUCAGGCAAGACACAUCUUGUCAUCUGUUGAAGAAUUCACAGCAGCUCAGGACAGCUCUGCGAUGGUGGGUGAAGAUGUCGGCUCCCUGGCUCUGGAGAGUAAGUCCCUGCAAAGCCGCCUUGCUGAGCAGCAGCAGCAGCACGCCCGGGAGAUGAGCGAGGUGACGGCGGAGCUGCACCACACACACAAGGAGCUGGAUGAUUUGAGACAACAUUUAGAUAAAUCUUUGGAAGAGAACAGUAGGUUAAAAUCGCUUUUGUUGAGUAUGAAAAAGGAAGUGAAGAGUGCAGACACUGCAGCCACGUUAAAUUUGCAGAUCGCUGGACUUCAAACAAGUGUGAAGAGGCUGUGUGGCGAGAUUGUGGAACUGAAGCAGCACCUGGAGCACUACGACAAGAUCCAGGAGCUCACGCAGAUGCUGCAGGAGAGCCACAGCUCCCUGGUCAGCACCAAUGAACACCUGCUGCAGGAGCUGAGCCAGGUGCGGGCGCAGCACAGAGCCGAGGUGGAGCAGAUGCACUGGAGCUACCAGGAGCUCAAGAAGACCAUGGCCCUGUUUCCACACAGCAGCGCCAGCCAUGGAGGCUGCCAGGCCUGCUGACUCCUGCCGAGAAGCUGGGCCACCCCUUAAGCUUCCUGGUAAAGUUACAUUGUCUGCACCUUUGUACUUCUUUAUUGAGUGUACUGGCUGGCAAGAGUUCUCUCUUCUGUUGGUAAUUAUUUAGGAUUUUUGGAAUGUAUUCAGGACCUGUAGCUUGGUUUUCUAAAGCACCUCGUAAAAUGAUAUGAUUACUCCAAGCCCUCUGCAUGUUUUCAGACAGAACACAUUGACAUAUUUUGAGACAAACUGACUAUUAAUCUUGUAUCCAGUAUCCUGAGAUGAAGUAAAUGCAGUGUUCUACUGCCUGAUGUGAAAGAGAGCUAUGUAUGAUAAUUAAAGAAAAUAAUUUUCUGUGUAACAAGCAAUCUUUAUUUAAUAAACAAAUACAUUGUUCUGAAAAGUUAACUUUUUCAGUGGCUGUAUACAAAUUAUAACUGAGUUUGUCAUUGAGUUUUUUAUAGAACAAGCUGUGCACCAUGAUAGGUGAGUGGGAAUAAUUAAGUUCAAAGACUUAACACAAGUGACACUUAUAGAUGUGGGGGAAAAAACCUUAAAAAUAUUGUCUUAUGAUAUUAACAUAUCACAGCGGAAACAUCUACCCAAGCCCUGGCUCGCUCUCUUGUUUGCAGUGUAGUUCUGAAAAUUAUGUCAUAAUAGGACACAAAACUAGAUUUUUAGUUUGGAAACUUCAUAUCUUAUGUCAUACUUGCUGUGAUUGGUAAGACAAGGUCAUUUUUUAAAUGACGUUCAACUGAUUUGGGAAGAAUGAGCAGGCCUAAGAAGAAAAUGCUCUGUGCUAGCUCUGUGUGUGUGUGUGCCCUUGCUGUGUGUGUGUGUGCCCUUGCUGUGUGUGUGUGCUGUGUGUGCGCUAGUGUGCGCUUGCUGUGUGUGUGUGCUAGCUGUGUGUGUGUGCUGUGUGUGCGCCUAGUGUGUGUGUGCUAGCUGUGUGUGUGCUAGCUGUGUGUGUGUGCUGUGUGUGCUAGCUGUGUGCGCUUGCUGUGUGUGCUCUGUGCGCGUGCACUUGCUCUGUGUACUAGCUGUGUGUGCAUGCUAGCUGUGUGUGCGCUUGCUGUGUGUGUGCUAGCUGUGUGUGCAUGCUUGCUGUGUGUGUGUGCUUGUGCGCUUGCUGUGUGUGUGUGCAGUUGCUGUGUGCUAGCUGUGUGUACGCUUGUGUGUGCGCUGUGUGUGCGCGCACGCACCCUGUGUGUGUGCUGUGUGUGCACGCGUUGUGUAUGUGCACUUGCUAUGUGUGUGCUUGUGUGCUAGCUGUGUGUGUCUGCUAGCUGUGUGUGUGUGUGCUUCUGUGUGUGUGUGUGUGUGCGUGUGGAUUGUAUCCCUGGGGAAAUCAGAGGUGGGACUCUGCUGUCUCUUCCCCGAAGAGGACUUGCUAGGCUUCAGGCUGCCCUCUUGUGUCACCUCUCUGUCCAGUUGUGGUCCUAACAGGAAAAUGUGUCAUACCAAAUUUAUUUUCUGUAGGGUUGGGAUGGGGUUAAUUUGUCAUCACGUAAUUUAUGUAUGUAAGAGUAUUAGAAGAUGUUAAUAUUAAUCCACUUUAAGCUUAUAGAUGCUUACCUCGUUUGGGUUUCAUUGAGCUUCUUGGACCUGUGAGUUCAUAUUUUUCACCAGAUUUGGCAAAGUUGCAGCCACUACUCAUAUUUCUUGUCUGACCCCGUCUCUCACUUCUUCCUCCCUGUCCCCAUCUGGGACUCUAGUUAGCUUUCUGUUAGACUGUGAUACUGUCUCUCAGGUCACUAAACGUGAUGCUUUUUCAUCCUUGUUCUCUCAUCCUUUCCUUUAGGUGGUUUUAUUGUCCUGUUGCGAGGCUUACUAAUCUUUUCUUCCACUUGCCUAAUUUGAUGUUAAGCUUGUAUAGUGAAUUUUUUAUAUCAGAAAUUAGGUAUAUUUUUGUUCUAAAAUUCCAUUUGAGGCUAGGCGGGGUGGCUCACACCGUAAUCCCAGCACUUUGGGAGGCUGAGGCAGGAGGAUCACUUGAGGCCAGGAGUUUGAGACCAGCCUGGCCAACAUGGCGAAACUCCAUCUCUGCUAAAAAUGAAAAUUAGCUGGGCAUGGUGGUGGGCACCUGUAGUCCCAGCUUCUUGGGGGGCUGAGGCAGGAGAAUCGUUUGAACCUGGGAGGCGGAGGUUGCAGUGAGCCAAGAUUGCAGCACUGCACUCCAGCCUAGACGACAGAGCAAGACUCCGUCUCAAAAAAAAAACAAAAAAACUCCAUUUGAUUUUUUUCAUUAGUUUUAUAUCCCAUUAUGUUCACGUUUCCAUUAACUGCUUAACCAUGUUUUUAACAGGUUUACUAGAAAUUCCCAACUGUUCCAAAGUGGUGGUACCCGCAGGCCCGACUGCUAGUUGUGUAUGACCACGUCUGCCGGUCCAUGUUUUCAGCACCCAUUGCCUGAAGUGUUAGCACCUUCACUCCGGCACUGAACUUCCCAGCCCUGCCGUGGAAGCUGCCUGCCAGGUCCUCCCCAUCCUCAGGUGGAGGCUUCUCUGUUGAGGGGCCUCGGAGACCGCCCCCCAGCCCUCAGCGGACCAUGCUGGCUGGGAGCUCCGCCCUGGGGCUUCUGCUCUGCUCAGGUAGGGGGAGUCCUUCCACGGAGCUGUGGCCGCAGCAGGUGCACUCUUGGGAGUCGGGGAGGCGGGUGGUGCUCAUGCGUGCCAGUGAGGGAGGGGCCUCGCCACCCUCCUGUACUGUGAGCCUGGCCCUGGGCAGCCCUCUGCCCUGGCCAGAGCCUGACCGUAGCCACGGGCUAACAGGCUCUGGAAAAGUUUCCCCAGGACUGCCGCAGGCUCAUCCGCAGGUAGACUCCAGAACCACGGCCCAGCAGGUCACACGUGUGGCUGUGGCUGUGUGCGUGCCAAGGGACAGUGGCAGUGUGCCAUUGUGACAGCGGGUGGCCACACCCGUCAGCCUCCCCAGGAGGGAGCAGGAGCGCCGGCUUCUCCCCAGGUGCAGACAGGCAAGGGCGGGCCGCCUGGGUGUGUCCUGGCAGUGUGGAGUGUCCUGGAUGGGCUCUGCUCAGCCCCCUGCUGGCAGAGAAACCCCCACAGACACUGCAGGACUGGGGGUCCUCCCUAGUGUCCUGCUCUCCGGCGGGGGGGAUUGGCCAGGAGAGGUUAGGCUGAGCCAUUUUGGGAGAGUUGAAGAAGGUGCUUGGGCUGUGGCAAUGGGAGGUCUGCGAGCAAACAGGGUGCAGCUAGUGAGGACGGGCGAACGGGAGGGCCGGGCAGAGGCUCUGUCACGCGGUGAGGCGAGGAGUGUCUCGGCACUUCGUGUCUCUUGCCUGGCAACACCACAGGGACCGGACAUUCUGAAUCUUCCCAGACCCGCUCUGAGAACAUAGGCAGCCACCGCAUCUUCUCAGGAAAGCAAAGCGAGCCUACUCUACCCUCACAGUCCAAGCCACUGUGGUCAGCCGGGAAGCCGCCCACUGCCCCUGACGGCUUUCGUUUUACCUAGGUUGCCCUUGGCACAGAGCUGGCCUGUAGGCAUGUGUGCACAGGUGUGUCCAUGUGACCGGCUUCCCCACACAUGUGCCAGGCGCCCAGCACCCCCGCCAGGUGGCCUCACUCUGCCCUCUGCCCAGGAAAGCAGGAAGGCCCCGUGGUGUCCGCUGCACACAGGACAGGCCUCGGGCCCCACAGACACCUCCCACGUCCGGUGUGGGGCCAAUUCCGUGUUAGUUGCCUGCUGGUUGGGGUUAGCUCCUGCCACCCUCAGGGCUCCUGGAAGGUGUCUGCCGCUCAGGAGGUCAGCACAGCCUCCUGUUGCCAUGACAGCCAGCUGCUUUAAAACGCCCCUUUGACCUGCAAACCACGUGCCCAGUGUGGUGUGAUCCGCGAGACACUUUGGAAAUGGCUGAGGACGAGGCAGGUGUAUUAGGAGGGUCAGCGAACUGGGGCCCAAACCUGGUUUGAGAGGGGAGUGCUGGGGGCAUCCGGUAGGAGGAGGGGCAGGAGGGAGGCCUGGGCCUGGCCGCCCCCCAGCCCCCUCUGGGGCACCCGUCUGAGUUCUGCCCCAGUUAGUACAGGAAUGUAAUGAAGUGCGAGGUGACAGAGUCCCUGCUCUGGGGACACCGGCAGUGCCGCGAGGCAUGGAGCGGGGGCUACUUGCCCCCUUGCACCUUCUGGUCGUAGGUGCCUGCGUGCUUGUAGCCGGACACAUAGCCUGACUCGUCCACCAGAUCCACGCGGCCAGCCUUGCCCUUGCCCUUGCCAGAGGGGUCGAAGCGCUCCUUGUGGGAGCCCGUGAACUUGGUGGUGUCCGUGAGCCUCGACACUGUGGGCGACGAGAUGGCUUUCUGCAAGAGGAGCAGGAGGAAGGGGGCAGGCCCCGCCUUCCAUCCCCGCCCUGCUCACCGUCACCCCUGAGAUGAUGGGCGCCUUGCCCUCGAUGAGCCUGUGCACCUCGCGAACGGCCUCCUCGCUGCUCUUGUCUUUGAAUCGCUUCUUGGCGAGCUCCUCCAGCGCCUCCUGGAACUGCUCAAAGAUCUACCACAACUAACCCAAAGUGGGGUUUUUCAGUGUUUAAAACAAGAGAUCCUGUGGAUGAGGCUCAGCUCUGCAAAAGGCACCUGCAUUUCACCAGGGAAGCCUCUGGACAGCGCGAGAAAGGCUGCACCCAGCAGGCCAAGCAUUCCGAGGGCACUCCCAGCUGCAGAAUCCACAGUGACCAAGAGUCAGGGGACAAAUGACCCAUAAAACCCCAGCAAGCCUUUCCAGAAGUCAGUGAGCAGAGGGCCUAGAAUAGCCAAAACGAUUUCAAGAAAUGAGAACAGAGUCAGAAGACUGACUACCCAACUCCAAAGCUCAUCGAGGCUUGACUGCAAAGUGGCAGCGACGUGGGCACGGGCACGCGGCCAGCCCCGCAGCCCAGGGGGAGUCUGGCUCAGCCACAUGCAUGCUGCCCCCCCGAUGUCUACAGGUGCAGAGGCAAGCCAGAGAGAAAGGACUGUUUCUUCCACAAGUGGAGCUGGAGCAACUGGUGAUCCCUGUGCAAAUUAAAAUGCACUUUGGUCUAUACUGCACACUAUAUACAAAACUAACUCAAAAUAGAUGACGGUCCUAAUUAUGAAACUAAAACUUCUAGAAGAACACCAAAGAGAAGAUCUCUGUGACCUGGGGUUAGGCGAAGAUUUCUUAGAAAUGGCAACAAAACAUGGCCUAUAGUGGAAAAAAUGGAUGAACUAGACUUCAUCAAAACGUUCGAAACUCUGCUCUCAGAAGACACCGUUAAGGGAAUGAGAAGACAAGCCACAGACUAGGAGACAUGCCUGAGAAAGGACUUGUCUCUGAGAUACACAAAGGAACCUUAAAACUCAGCAGUAAGAAAAAAAAUCCAUGUGAAAAGACGGGCAGAAUAUUUGAAGCAGACACCACCAGAGAAGACACGUGCAUGCAGACAAGCACACGGAGAGGGGUCCGCGUGGGCCCCAUCAGGGAAGUACAGACAAGCACACGGAGAGGGGUCCGCGUGGGCGCCGUCAGGGAAGUACCGACAAGCACACAGAGAGGGGGCCGUGUGGGCGCCGUCAGGGAAGUACCGACAAGCACACAGAGAGGGGGCCGUGUGGGCGCCGUCAGGGAAGUGCGGACAAGCACACAGAGAGGGGGCCGUGUGGGCGCCGUCAGGGAAGUACCGACAAGCACACAGAGAGGGGGCCGUGUGGGCGCCGUCAGGGAAGUACCGACAAGCACACUGGAGAGGGGUCCGCGUGGGCCCCAUCAGGGAAGUACCGACAAGCACACGGAGAGGGGUCCGCGUGGGCCCCGUCAGGGAAGUACCGACAAGCACACGGAGAGGGGUCCGCGUGGGCGCCGUCAGGGAAGUACCGACAAGCACACAGAGAGGGGGCCGUGUGGGCGCCGUCAGGGAAGUGCGGACAAGCACACGGAGAGGGGUCCGCGUGGGCGCCGUCAGGGAAGUACCGACAAGCACACAGAGAGGGGGCCGUGUGGGCGCCGUCAGGGAAGUGCGGACAAGCACACUGGAGAGGGGUCCGCGUGGGCCUCGUCAGGGAAGUACCGACAAGCACACAGAGAGGGGGCCGCGUGGGCGCCGUCAGGGAAGUGCGGACAAGCACACGGAGAGGGGGCCGCGUGGGCGCCGUCAGGGAAGUGCAGAUGGAAACCACAGCGAGGCCCCUGCACACUCUCCAGGGGGCUCAGACAAUCAAAUAAACUGCCGGCACCUCGAGCUGAGCAGGCCGCGGGGUGGGGGCCUCGUCCACACCCGGCCGAGCAACGCGGCAGAGCCACUGUGGACAGCUUCUCAUCACAGCCAAAGGUGGCCCAGCAGUCCCGUUCCUGGGUCCUUGCUCAAGAGAAAUGAAAACAGAGGCUCACACAUAAACGCAAAUGUUUACCACUGUUCUGCUCGUAGUCACCAAACCCCAAACAAUCCAGUGCCCUUCAGCAGCGGCCAGACCACAGUGCUGUGAUGUGUGCGCACGUGGACAGCACCCCCACCCCUCGAGAACAAGCCCAGGAUACGCACCCAACGCGGUGGGUGCCAAGUGGCCAGGCUUGGAGCCAGGCACGGAGGUGCCGCUGGGUGAUUCCCAGACCCCAAGGCGGAUGCUGUGUUUAAACAGCACCUGAGGGUUCCCAUACACUUUACACGCGUGUCCUAAAGACACAACAGACACCAUCAACAGCGCUGAGCCAAAGAAGAAAUCGCGCUGAGAAACACACCAAGUGCUCGGGGUCCCACAGCUCAGACCCUCACGCCUCAUGGGGUCCCAGGGAGGGGAGCGGAGGCCUCGCUGUGUCCGGAGGGGGCUUUGGGGAGACAGAGCCCCAGGGCGGGGCCUGGACUGCUGAGGGCAGCCACGCAGGGCACAUUCCAGACCCGCCGGCCAUAGGGCGCUGUUGUCCAGCAGCAUCCCCCAGGGGGCGCUGGUGAGCCCGGUGAGCCGGAGGUGCCCUGGGCAGCUCUGUGGCGUGGGGGUCCGCGGUGUUGGGGGUGGAUUUAGCCCCUUGACGCGCUCGGCGUGGACACCCGCACGUUCCCUGUGGUGCUAGAAGAGCCAGGCCACCCCAGGCAGCCCACAGUGCCUGGAACUGACAGUGCCCAUUGGGCCCUGUGGGGGUGUUGACUCUCUGGGGCCCUUGGGGCCUCUGUCUGUCCUGGGCCGUCAAAGGCUCUCCUGUCUUCUAUUCCCACCCUGCCCAAGCUGACAUGCGGACGCCAGGCCUGACUGCCAGCCUGGUGACCAGUGCUGAGGCACGCAGCCCUUUCUGACGGCCUCGGAGCCAGGCACCACCAGCAUGAGUCACUCGGCGGGAGGGGGAUGGCUGAGGGGCUCCCCCAUCAGAGGCGACAUUCAGAUCCGGACACCUGCUCUGCGCGCUCCCCGAGUGUCUCGGGGAAAGGGCGCCCGGGUCUCUGCCCCACACGGGCGGGGAGCUCUCCCCAGGAGACCCGGGUGCCCCCCGCCUGGGGCAGUCCUCAGGAGUUCUAGGACAGCGGUGCCUGCCUCUUCCCCAGAGACACUCAGUCUGGCUGCCCGGCUCUCCUGACAUAGAGUGGGCCUGUCCUCCAGAGACCAGGGUGCUGGAGGAGCCUCCGAGUGUGGAGCUCGGCAUCCUCAUUGCCCAUGCUCUCCCCAGCCCGGCGCCCUGCCCCAAAGCCGGCCCAGCAGGACGCAGCCGCUGCUCAUACACGAUGCCCUGCGGGGCCUGGACUUGCUUCCCAGGCUCUGAGUCCCCUGGCCUCUGGGCCUGGUUCAGUCUCUCAGGGACACUGGGACCCGGCCUGGGGCCUCCAGGAGCUGGGCUCAGGCCAGGACAGCCCUCCGAGGACUGAGGCCUGUUCCUCCGGGGCGGACGUCACAGGCCCCGCUGGGCUCGGGACUGUGCAUCCAGCACCCUUGUGAAUCAGGAAUGCCCUCCCAUGGUGCCCUCUCUGAGGGGCGGGGGCCGGCGGGCGAGGUGACAGCUACCAGCUCCCCUGGGCUCUCUGGGCCUGCAGCUGCUGUGGCUGGAGUGCCCUGUCCAGAGGCUGCCACAGGUGGGAAGCUGGGGGCUGUGGAGGGGAAUCUCUGGGGAAACAGCCUCUCCCUGUACUUAGGCGAGUCUGAGAGAGAGGGGCUGCGGCUCCCCCAGGGCACCAACCUCUGGGAUCUUCCAUUAGCCCCUGAGACCUGAGGAGGCUGGGAAGGACUCCCUGGCUGCUGGGCCCCACGGGGGGAGGGGGAGCUUCUGGGGAGGUUCCUACCUGGUAGGGACGCGGCCUUAGGGGAGCCCUGUCUGGCAUCGCCAUCCUGCACGUCGCUCCGAGUUCUCACUGCUCCAGGAGGGUCCAGUGGUCCCGUUCCAGCAGGACCCAGCCUUGGGGUUCCCCAUGCCUGUUGGCCGCCCCUGCCUCCCGCAAGCCCCAGCAAGAUACAGAGGACCUAGAGCAACGUUUCCCGGGGCCGACAGAGGUCGGUGGCAAGCCCUCCAGGCCCUGCCUAUUCUCCCCUCAUAAGUGACUCCACCAGCAGCUGAGCACCUGGGGGCAGGUGAGGUGAUGUCUGGCCACCUGAGAGGGCUUCUCCCCUCAUCUCAGGAAACCGGAGCCCUUCCUGCACCCUACUUGGCUCAGAGGAUGGAUGGCAACGUCCACUGGGCCACGGCAGCUCAGGCCCCAGGGCGGGCUGAGGGCCAGGGCCCUCCCAUUGCUGCACCAGCUCUAACCCCAGGCACACCCACCAUGAAGCCCCCACACAGCCGGUCGGGGGGCUGCCUGAGCUCCGGAGGUCUGGCUACCGAAGGCUCCCCCCUGCCUGAGGGGCCGCCUGGGAUCAGCGCACUGUCUCCCUCUGGGCGCACACCCUGCGCUUGCUGCUAAUUAAUUUUGCGUUGCUGCCGGCCUUUUCGUUUUCCUGGGGAGGGGCGGGGGUGGGGCGUGUGUAGUCACCGCCCUGUGGACAUCACUAGGAAGAGGUGGCCCUUGGUGGGACGUGGACUUGGGGCCCAGAGGGACCCCGGGCAGAUCUGAGGGGCCCGACCUUCUCUAGGGGGCCCCAGGGGCUCGGCUGCCUCCAUCCACCCCAGUCUCGGCCUGGGCAGGGCUUUGGUCUGUGCACCUGAAGUCAGUUUCUGGCUGUUUGUUUGGAGAUCACCUUCUCAAAUGACCUGUGUUGCCUGGUCAGGCUCAUGGGGCAAAGUGGACAGCCAAGGCCACGCCCACCACUGGCCAAGCGCAGGAGACGGGUGCCUGUCGCCGCACAGUGCUCUGGGGAUUGCUGGUGCUGCCCGGCCUGCAGGGUACAGGAGCCACAGGCCUUGACUGUGAGGCCACAAGCUCCUGAACCCUCAGCCACAGACGUCCAUGGCCAAGGGUCCCCCCGCAGGGGCUCCACUCUGCGGAAGCCACGUUCAUCCUGCCCUGCCAGGCGUGGCCACUAGAGGCUCCCCAAAGACAGAACUGGCCCCAGGGCUCCAGAGCCGCCGAGUGCAAGCCCGGGACAGGGUGGCACCCACAGCAAUGGAGGGACAGGGUUGGGUGUGGGGAGUGCAGCCCACCCUUCCCCCGGGCUGGGUACCACGGGGGAGGGGGAGGGGAGCAAUGCAGCCCUGAGGCUCCUGGCCCCUUCCAGGGAAGCUGACACCUGCUUUUCUGGGAUGGACAGACAGGAGGACGUCACACACAGUGCUCUGAGGACCUCACUUGCCCUGUGGCGGCUGCCCUCCAAACACACUGUGACCUGGAUUCUCUCCAAACCUGGGUCCUGCUCCUGGGAGGUGGUUGGGUUGGCUUCCGUACUGGGAACAGUCCGAAGACUUUAGGACAAAGUGUCCUACCGGCCCUCCACACUUGGGGUGACCACAGACCCCAGUGCCGGCUGGCCGGGGGGGUGUACCAGGCUCAGCAGCCCUCCACGCUCGGGGCAACCGCAGACCCCAGGGAGCCUGGCCCUGCUGUUCUCAGUCUCCCACUGGCCCUGGCUUCCUUCUAACCAGCGUCCAGGUAUCAGUCUAACCCCCAAGCCAAGCCACCACCCAGUAUCCACCCAGGUGUCUAUAGGAAACGUCAGUGCAUUUACUUGGGAAAAUACACCACACCCAGCACACAAGCGUGGGUCCUGGGGGAGGCCAGGGCUCCCAGCCAGCUGAGACCGCAGCCCAGCCCUCCUUCCUCUGCCUCAUCGGCUGGGUGCCCCCACCUGAGCUAGAUGGACCCAUAGGGGGCCAGUGAGCAAGGCUGGCAGACCCUCGCCCAGAGGCUGGUGGUGUUUGGUGCAGUUGGGGAGGCAGCAGCUGAGCCUGACCCCAGGGGUCCUGAGGCACCCAUGGCAUGGGCCCCUCCCCAGGCUCGAGGAGGCGCUGGGAGAUUCGCUGUCCAUGGCUCUACCGGGCCCCACUCCCACCGCCCGUGGUCCGGUCCCGCCUGUGCACGCUAUGCCUCCAUUAAUAUUUUAAAGCUGCCACCGCACGCUCUUUGCAGGAGGGAGUCAUUGUCUGGGUUAACAGUAGGCUUCAACAAAAACCUGGCGUAAGGCUGCAAGAAAUUUGUUUAAGAUUUAACACAUAGUAACAUCAAAACAAACAAGCGCUGCCAUGGCAACGAGGACUAAACAAAGGCUCGCAGAUACCCCGAGCUGGCGCCACGCCGGUGGAGCCAUGGCAACCUGCCCUGAAAACAGAAAUCGGUAGACUUUUUCUCCACAAGUCCUGUCAGAGUCAGCAGCUUUCUGCAGUACCGAAGGCCACUUCCUCACGGUCCCCAAGCUCCUGAGGGAGGCAGAGGCUCCCACAAGUGACAGUGGGCACCCCCUCCCCAAAAUGCAAAACAAAAGCAACUCCCACAGGCCCGCCGCCACCACCCCUUGCUUUCCCCGGAAAUCGAAGGAAAAUCUCUAGUGUCCCCAACGCCUCGUGGUGGCCCUGCUCCUCUCUCUUCCUGAGACAAGGGUGUGAGUUUUUAGGCCCCUUGCUGCUGUACACCUGGGAGGUCAGGACCCCGUGCCAGGAUCACAGGGACCCCCCGAGGGGAGUCCAAGCUGCAGGAGGGAAGGACAGUUUGAGGGUGGGAGAGAGGAGGAGGUGGGGGCAGCCCUGGGGGGCCAGGGUCACAGGGGUCCAUGGCUGCAGGUGAAUGGGGAGGGGGGGAGGUCAGAAUCCCUUGGCCUCCCCUCAGGCCGGAGUCCCAGUCCUGGCCACCUGAGCUGCUGCCCGCAGGACAAUCUCCCACACGGCGCCCACUCACGGUGCCCAGCCUGCCGACCAGGCUGCCCAGGACCGGGUCUCAGCCUCAACCCCUCGCUGGGCUUGGGCCACAGCUGUCUGCUCCCCCAGACCUUGACCCUCAUGGUCAGCCAAGGCUGGCACACCCCAAGGCUGGUCCCCGGCCCCACACUGGGGAGGUGAAUGUGCUGGAGCAGGGGGCCAAGCUUUAGCCCCCCAAGCGCCUGAGCAGCUCCAGCCCUGCCUCUGGGAACAGGCCCAGACCAGCUGGGGCUCCUCCGGCCUCCUGGGGUGCCAGCACCCCCACAAGCAGGCAGGGCUCCCAUCAUUCUCCAAAUGAGCCACAGCCACCCAGCCCCACCCACCGCAGGGAGAGUUCUGCAUGUGUGUGCAGGCGUGUGUGUGCACAUGCGGCCAUGUGCAUGCACACAUGCGCCAUAGUUUGAAAGCAACUUUCUGCAGAAGGAAUCACAGCCGGCACUGCACUUGGUGUGUCCGGGCCAGCGCCAAGGCUGUGCACAUGGGGCCGGCCCUGCAGGGCUGACGGCCCCUGGACAGGCUCUUCCUACCUCCCGCCCAGCCCUUCUAGGAGCUUCACCCACAAGCACCAUCUCCACACCGCUUUGCCCCGGGUCUGCUCCUGUGUAUCCUGGAACACACAUUGGGCGGCACAGAGGGCACCCAGGGACUCGUCCCAGAUGUGUCCACACGCCCGAGCCUGCUGAGGAGCAGCUGCCAGGGCCCAGGAGCACGGGGCUGGGUCCCCUCCAAACAAGGACACCUGAGGGGGAGGAGGAGCACUGGGGGGCACAGGGGCCCUGGCAGCCAAGGGGAGGAGCUGCCCUGCCCUUGCCCACGCAGGCUCUGGACCUGGCGGCCACACUGCGAACCCCACCUGCUUCUGCGUGGGCUAAAUAUAGCCGACCCAGUUUCCCUCUCCCGGUCCGAGUGCCCGGGACACGUCCCCUUGGCAGAGUGAGUUCUGGGCUCAGGACAAGGGCACUGUCUGUGCCAGAGGCUCUGGCCCCUGACCUCCCGGGCACAGCCCAGGUCACUGCUGCCUGCCCAUGGCUGGUGACCCACCAGAGCGGCCCUGGUCACCAGGACCUGCCAGCAGCUGGCUGGGGCCAUCUACACAGGCCCACACCGCAUGGCCCGCUGCUGCAGGAGGCUGCAGGUUUCCAGCAGGGGAUGGCAGGCUGGUCUGUCCUCCAGGCAGAGGCUGCAGGUUUCCAGCAGGGGACAGUGGGCUGGUCUGUCCUCCAGGCAGCGGCUGACAUAAGCCCUGUGGAUGAUGUGGGAGCUCCAGCGAGCCUGUGGGAGCUGCCCCUUGCCAAAGAGCCCACAAGCAAGGCCUGUACUGCAGAGUCAGGCGCCAGUUGCUUCAGCCACAGUCCUGAGGGAGGUGCAGCCCUGAGAGUCAGUCCACAAAGGAUCUGUGGCCGGGGGAGCAGUGAGGGGGGCACAGUGUGGCCGGGGGAGCAGUGAGGGGGGUACAGUAUGGCUGGGGGUGCAGUGUGGCCAGGGGUGCAGCAUGGGGGGUUCAGUGUGGUCAGGGGUGCAGCACGGGGGGUACAGUGUGGCCAGGGGUGCAGUGUGGCCAGGGGUGCAGUGUGGCUGAGAAUGCAACAUGGAGGGUACGGUGUGGCCAGGGGUUCAGUGUAGCCGGGGGUGCAGUGUGGCUGGGGGUGCAGUGCAGGGGGUACAGUGUGGCCGGGGGUGCAGCCCAGGGGGUUCAGUGUGGCCAGGGGUGCAGCGUGGGAGGUACAGUGUGGCCGGGGGUGCAGUGUGGCUGGGGGUGCAGUGUGGGGGUGUGCAGUGUGGCCGGGGGUGCAGCGCAGAGGGUGCAGUGUGGCCAGGGGUGCAGUGUGGCCAGGGGUGCAGCACGGUGGGUGCAGUGUGGCUGGGGUGCAGCACAGGGGGUGCAGUGUGGCCAGGGGUACAUUGUGGCCGGGGCUGCAGUGUGACCAGGGGUGCAGUGUGGCCGGGGAUGCCGUGUGGCCGGGGGUGCAGUGUGGCUGGGGGUGCGGUGUGGCCAGGGGUGCAGCAUGGGGGGUACAGUGUGGCCGGGAGUGCAGUGCCAGAGGUGCAGGCUGUUGGACGGACCCUCGAGGGCUGAGCCCCAGCCCUUGUUGGGCCCCUGCUGGUCCCCUUGCUCUGGCAGGCUCCUUGUGCCUUCCUGGUCUCAAGGGGCCCCAGGGAUGAGUGGUCCUGGGUUAGUGUGGGCUCCAACCGCUAAGGUGUUGGCAAAUGAUGGCCCUUUCCGAGGCCGGGGAGCACAAGGUUGCAUGACUACCUACACAGAGGGGCCAGCCACAGCCUCCUCUCACACCGGCCAGUGGCUGAGCCCAUGAGGACACUGAGGCUGGGAAGCCACAGAGGAGGUUGGCGGGGCCACUGGGACUGGACAGGGUCAAGGAUGAGACCAGCUCGCACCCGGGGCCCUGGAUGGAGCCUCCCCUCCAGCUUCUCUGGGACUGAGGCUGGGAGCUGUCAGGAAGACGAACAGGACUCGCUGGCCCUGGUUGCCUCUGCCGUCCCCUAGAGCUGGGGGAGCCUGCAAGGCAGUCAGCUGGAGAGAGGGUCCGGGUUCAGGCAUCCUUCUGAGCAGUUUCAUGGCUUUUCUGGCAUAACUUUCCAAACCCCAAAUGCCCUCGGAUGCACUCAGAUGCGCCGUACACAACAGGAAGCUCAGCAGGACACGCAGUCUAGGAACAUGCACGACCCAGGAGACACCCAAGACCCAGGGGAUGUGUGACCCGGGAGACACAUGUGACAUCGCCACGGAGCACAGCAGAGACGGAACAGCUGCAAAGGUCACGGCGCCCACCCAGAGCUGGUAGAUGGGGCGCUGGCGCCGCAGAGGUGGGCCCCACAGCCUUCCACACAGGGGCAUCUGACCCACGGCCCGGCCCCUUGCAAAGCCAAGGCCGCAGAGGGGGAAGGUGCAGGAGCUCUGAGAUGAAAGAGGUGAUGAGUUUGCGGCAAUGUAGGAAUGAAAUACAUCGGCCACAGGAGGACGCAGGUGCAAACCACCGAAAUAAAGCCAUUGCCACACAGGCGGACAGGA